ACGGUUUGCAAACAAUUUCUCUUUAUUCUAAGACUCUGUAAUUCUCCAGGUUUCCAAAGAAUUUCAGUGCUGAAGUAUUGUGAACCUGUGAGGUACCCUAUUGUGAGACAGAUGGGAAUUGGUGGGGCAGAGGGAGAGAUUGAGAGAAUAUCCUUGGCUCCUUUUAUCCAGUAUUUUUAUCUUACCUUGGGUAAAAUUAGAUUGUUGCUAAUAAUAACCUAAAAGAUAGUAAAAAAGUCAAAUUGAUCCUGAUAAAUUAGAAAAGUAGUGCUGUAAGCAUGGGCUGUUUAAUAGGAGUAGAUUCAUGCAUUCUUAAGGACCAGAAACCUCCAGUGCAAUAUCGAUAAGGAAGAUUGGUCAGGGACACACAGCAGAAACAUACUGCUAUUGAACAUAAGAUGGACAUGAAUAGGAGUGUAUUGUUCUUGAGGAAAAGGGCAGUGUUGUGCUAAAUGUGUUAGAUGUGUUAGAUAUGACAUGAAAAGCUAGGACAUAGUUCAUUUUACUUGUUUGCUUGCUUGUUAUUAAAACCUUGGAUAUCCAGUUUUGGUCAUUGUGCCUCAAAAAUGAGAAGAUCCAUUGAACAGAAGGAACAAAGAGAUGUAAAGCAAUCUAUACUUCUCAACCUCUACUUUCCAAUUUGAACAUUUUUAUUUAUUUAUAUUUAUUCACUUAUUGAGAAAAGUCUGUAAGCAUCUUUAUUGUUUUGUGGGGUGGAGGCUGGUGCUCAGGAGCUUUUGGCGGAUUGGUGGGGCAGGUCCCCUUCCUCUUCAUCCUCACAGGCUUCUGGCUAUGCAGACUGGUGCUGGCUCUGUGGAAGCUGCCAUGCAUAGAUCUGGGUGAUGGUACUUCUUGUGGAGCAUGUGCUGGAUGCUGUUGAGAGUGGCCCCGGAGUUCUUGGUGGUGGCGAUUUGCAUAUAGGAGGUGGUUUGCUUUUGUUGGGCAGUUUAUCACCUUCAUGACCACCACAACACCUUUGCUGUUGGCUCCACACCCACAGUCAGUUUUAACAGGAGUUUCAGUGAAUCAGUUAGUUGUAACCAAAGGAGUUGCCGGCCUUCAGUUUAUUGGAUUCGGUGCUGUGUGUCUGCCUAUUCCUCUUGAUGGGGAAACUGGAGCAGUUCCCUACAGUCCAGCCAUUUCAGGUGCCCAAUUAUGUCUCCUCUACCUGUGAUGUUCAGAGAUGAGAAGAGCCACUUUUACUUUUUCACUGUAAAUUUUUAUUUAAUGUCAGCCUUGCUUGCCGAACUAUAAACUCUGUGAGGAGGUCUGUAGUGCUCACCAUUGUUUCUUUAGAGCUGAAUACGUAGCCUGACACACAGUAGGCUUUCAAUAAAAAUUUAAUUUACCAGAAGUGGAAAAUGAGUUUUAUGAAGAAAAUUUCAGAAAACUGAGUUCAUUUUUCAACACAAGAGAUGACCAAGGGGUAAUAUGUUCCUUCAGGUUCAUGAACAGCCUGCAUGAAUAUGCCAAGUAGUUGUUUUGUAACUGUGGAAGAUUGGCUAAGAGGAGAUGGAUGGAAAGUAAAGUCAGAAAGACCUUAUUGAUUUAGGCCAGUGGGAGAAGUGUUGGAGUAUCUGCUCUGGAGAAAAUGCUCUUUUCCGGCUAGUUUUGUUAAUUAUGUUUCUGAAAAGGGGGGCUAGAUUGGAUGGUCUUUACCAGGUUUCUUCCCCUUCUGAUUCAGGGACUUCAGGAGGUUUGUGGUAACCUGAGAAAGUAGCCUGAGGUAUUAUGGUGCUGGAGUUCUCCAUAGGGUGCUUAGCAGACCACCUUUAUCUCCCCAUACAUUGCGUUUUUCCAUAUGUGAGCUGAGAAUAAGCUGGUUGCCUUUCAGUGAUCUGAAAUUAUAGAUGCAUUUCUUGGAAGCUUUAUUUUUUUUAAUGGCUAAAAUUGAGUAGUAUCGCUAUUGCUGUCUGUAGACUACCACUUGCUAUUCCUGUUUAGAGUUUACUGGGCUUGGUAAGUUGGAAGGGUAACAGGAGCACGUUUGUGAUUUUUUUUUUUUUUUUUUGAGACGGAGUCUCGCUCUGUCGCCCAGGCCGGACUGCGGACUGCAGUGGCGCAAUCUCGGCUCACUGCAAGCUCCGCUUCCCGGGUUCACGCCAUUCUCCUGCCUCAGCCUCCCAAGUAGCUGGGACUACAGGCGCCCGCCACCGCGCCCGGCUAAUUUUUUGUAUUUUUAGUAGAGACGGGGUUUCACCUUGUUAGCCAGGAUGGUCUCGAUCUCCUGACCUCAUGAUCCACCCGCCUCGGCCUCCCAAAGUGCUGGGAUUACAGGCGUGAGCCACCGCGCCCGGCCCACGUUUGUGAUUUAAACAACAACAACAACAACAACAACCAGUUAACGUAAUUGACAGCAGAGAAGUUCCAGGCAGAACAGUGGCUCUUUCGUUUUUCUUCUACACAUGGCUUUUUGCCAUCAGCAUCAGUGAAGACUUGCGGAAGGAGCUAAUGCUGCUUAUUUGCAGUUGUUGAACCUGUUUGCCUAUGGGACAUACCCAGAUUACAUAGCCAACAAGGAGAGCCUGCCAGAACUGAGCACAGCUCAGCAGAACAAGCUGAAGCAUCUUACCAUCGUGAGCUUGGCAUCAAGAAUGAAGUGUAUCCCCUACUCCGUGUUGCUGAAAGACCUGGAGAUGCGGAAUCUCCGGGAACUAGAAGACCUUAUCAUUGAGGCUGUCUACACUGACAUCAUCCAGGGCAAGCUGGACCAGCGAAACCAGCUGCUGGAAGUGGAUUUCUGCAUUGGCCGUGACAUCCGAAAGAAGGAUAUCAAUAAUAUUGUCAAGACCCUGCAUGAAUGGUGUGAUGGCUGUGAAGCAGUUCUACUGGGCAUCGAGCAGCAAGUUCUGAGAGCCAACCAGUACAAAGAGAACCACAACCGAACUCAGCAGCAGGUAGAAGCAGAGAUUGCUUGUUUUCAGAGGGAAAAACGUGAUGUCCCCCUCCUGAAUCUUAUAACAACAGCUUUCUUCUGGUUACCAACAUCAAGAAGACACUCAAAGCCACCGCAUCCUCCUCGGCUCAGGAGAUGGAGCAGCAGCUGGCUGAACGGGAGUGUCCCCCUCACGCUGAGCAGAGGCAGCCCACCAAGAAGAUGUCCAAAGUGAAAGGUCUGGUCUCCAGCCGCCACUAGGGCCGGCUGGGGCAGCUGGCACUCACCAGGCCUGGGUCAGGUGGGGAGGGGACACCAAGGGCCCAUUUCCUCCCCUCUCUACCUGCAGUGAGUUCCAGACCUGCCCGUCCCCUCACCAGCGCCUCCCCACCCUGUUGGUACUGUUCCAGAAAAACUGUUACUCCCCCUCACCCACUCCCUCCUUCCCCAGUUGUUCCCUUCAGACUCAGGGGCUCCACCAAUGCCAUCCCAAAACAGGGUCAGACACUGCCCAGCUUCCCUCCAGGAGGUUCUUGUCUCUGUGUAAGGGCUUGUCUCCCUCCCAGUUUUUCUUUUGCUCCACGUCAUUUUGUCAGGCUGGUUAUAAGCCGGAGGCAGCUUUAACCAGCCCCCAGGGAUGAUUGUGAAGGAGGCCCCUCCCCUUGUGAGGAGGGGGCACUCCUCUCCAGCCCCUGGUACCACAGUCCUCACGAUGGUGCAGUGAUUUCUAGCCAGGCGUCAAGAUGCGCUGCUUUCCCUCUCCUGCCUCAUCCCUUGUUGGCAGCUCCAGUUCAGGCCGUGGAGGGACGUGAUGCUGGGCUGUGUUUACUAAACCCACGGGUUUUCAGCCUCUUAAGCCCAGCUCCGAUCUCCAAUUAGUUGAGAGCGCUGGGUUGACUAACCUCUGGUAUCUGAGCACAGACAGAGGGUGCUGUGGGUCUGCUGGGUGGCAGAAAUGGUUCCUUCCGGCUUGGCGUUCUCUCCUGGCCACUCUUCCUGCUGCCUCUGACUACUCAGCCUUGUUUUCGGUGUGUAGGCCCCAGCUGCCCACUGGAACUGCCGGCUAAUGCUUGCUCUCCCAAGAUCUUUAACUCCUCCUGGCUGCACCUGGGUAGGGAUGGUGGCAUCGAUGCCCCUCUGUCUGCUGAAGGACCUGUUGCUGCUUCUGUCUUUUCACCCCUCCUUGGCUGAUGACCCAGAGCCCUCUGAUGAUGGCAUUCUCCUGGCAAGAGAAAAAGACUUAACUAGACUUCUGAACUUGAACAGUUUCAGGUUAUAUUUUAAUUUUUUUUUUUUUGUACAGGUUCUGAUUCUAAUACAUUUCAACAUGCUUUUGUCCCCCCUCGUGUCAAUAUUUGUUAUAGACUAAUCGCCGGGGAUUUUUCACCUGGUUGGAGGGUGGGGGUGGGGUGGGGUGUGUGUGUGUGUGUGUGUGUGUGUGUGUGUGUGUGUGUGUGUUUGUAGGUCCUGGACUGAUUAAAGUUCAUUGAGGAAAAAGCACAUUUUACAACAAAAAAAUAAAAGUGUAGAUUUAAUGUAUGUGACUGGGGUUUGGGGUUGCAUACCUGGUGGAUCUUGAGGGGCUGGGAUUAGGGUGGUUCAGGAAAAUGUGAUGCUGUUUCCCCAUGUUUAGCCAUGGUCAAAAAAUGGAUUUCUCCUUUUUCUAAAAUGUCCAGCAACUGCCUACUGUUGAUCAAAUGUUGAAGUAUUCUUGUUUCCCUUUUAAGCCAAUCCAUGUGCCCACAUAACAUUAUGCCCAAGUGGAGAGUUCACUUUAAUUUCCAAAGUAUGUUUCAUGCAGCCCCCUGUCAGCUGCUCUGUGGAAAAGGGGUUCUGUUAUGAAAUAAAUGUUGCACUCCCUGCAUCCCA